AUGUUAAAGCUUUACAACGGCCUCUCGGAAGGGGAGGCGGUGAGACUCCUCGCGGGGACCGACCCCCUGGACCCCACUGAUCUGAACGGGGCACACUUCAACCCGGAAGUUUACCUAGACAAGCUGCCUAGAGAGUGCCCUCUGGCCCAGCUGAUGGACAGUGAGACGGACAUGGUGCAGCAGAUCCGGGCUCUAGACAGCGACAUGCAAACCCUGGUCUAUGAGAACUACGAUAAACCUCCCAGUGCCAAGUGUCGCAGGCCAGGGCCCGGCGUGUCCGCGGUGAGCGCGGGCGGCCAGCAGAGGGCGCCAGAGAGCCAGGAGCGGCCCGCGGAGGAGUCCGCGCCCGCCCUGAUGCCCAGCUCCGCGCCGCGCGGACCCACCGAGCCCGCGUUCAGACGCCCCAGCUCCGCCGACAGGCCGCUCGCGCCGGGUCCUUCCUCUUCCCCAGGUGCAGGCAGAGCCCCCAGAGCCAUGGCCAGCCCUUCCGGCAGCUCCGAAGCCACUGGCAAGCCCCGAGGCAGGGAUGGCGGGCCCAGGAGGGAGGAGGACGACGUCCCUCCCGAAGAGAAGAGGCUGCGGCUGUUGCUGGAGAGGGGAAGCGCGCAGCCCGAGGACUGCGAGGACGGGGAGGACGCGCCGCGGCCAGGCAGGAAGAAGACCGGCACCCAGACAGGUGGCGACGGCAGAGGAGGCUUCCGCUGGGACUAGGAUCAGGAUGUGGACACCCCCAAUCUGGACCGUCUAGCCGGGGAGGGCGUCAAGGCCAG